CAGGGAGGGCUGGGAGAGGGCUGGGCAGGUCAGCUUGAGGCCAAAGCCACAGGGGCUCAUUAUGCCAGGCCAAGGAGCUGGGAUUUCCUGCUCUGAGCCAUAGAGAGCCAGAGAAGGCUCUUGAGCAGGGGAGUGGCAUGAUCAAGAUGGCACUUAAGGAAGAAAAGUCUGAUGACUGUGGCCCAAAUAUUCGGAUGUGCUUCAUCACCUACUCCACAGACGGCCAGACUGUCUUGCCACUCACCUCAGACAAGUGAGUGCUGCUUUGAGCCCCAAAGGGAGGCCUGAUGAGCUUGGCCAGAGGGAGCUCCAGGGAGCUGAAGGGCUCCCGGAGACCUUGGUUGGGAGCCUGACAGCACACAGGGCAGGCCGGUCAGGGCAACUCACAGUACCCACCUGACCUUAGCCCCGGCUCCCCUGCAUCCUCCUACCCAUGGCUGCAAGGUUACCUGCAGGCCCCUGUGCUCCAGAAGUUCUCAGCCUCCCCCACUUCACGCUCCCCUGCCCUCUCUCCGCUCUGCCUCCUUCCCUGAAAGGUGGCUGUGAGGAUUCCCAGGGUGCAGGGGCUGGCAGGGCGGGGGUGUGUGUCCUGUGAACACACACCUGUGCUGGCUGCUGCUCUGUGCCUGUUCCCCCUGCCCUGACCAGUGUGGGAGGGAGACAGGGUCAAAGCUGGUGGUGGGAGUAGUGGGGCUUUAGUGCAGGGAUGCUGGCAGGCCCAGACUGGGGAGCCCCUGGGUGGGGUUCUGAGCUCCAGGGCAGGCUGGGAAAGUGGAGGGAGGCAGGAGGAACAAGCUCAGGAGGCUGGAGCCCAGGCCCAGCAGGGAGCACAGCAGAGUUCCUGUUUGGCCGGAGGUGAGGGCACUUCCAAUGCACAUGCCCGGAACUGGGCCCAGAGGAGAUGAAGCACAGAAGAGAGGGGCACAGAAAGUCAAGGAGGCCAGACACUCUAAGCAGAUUUGCUACUUCCUGUAUCAGGGAAUAGAAUAAAAAACGGUCUUGACCAACUUCAGAAAAUUGUGCCUGACGGUCACACAUUCAUGCAGGCAGGAUUUAGAAAGGCAAUUCAACAGAUCGAAAGUUUCAACUCCGGAAACAAGGUUCCCAGCAUGAUUAUUGCUAUGACUGAUGGAGAACUGGUGGCACAUGCAUUUCAGGACACUCUCAGAGAAGCUCAAAAGGCUCGGAAACUGGGGGCCAACGUUUACACCCUGGGUGUGGCUGAUUAUAAUCUGGAUCAGAUAACAGCAAUUGCAGACAGCCCUGGCCACGUGUUUGCAGUGGAGAAUGGCUUCAAGGCCCUGAGAAGCACCAUUGAUGCCCUCACGUCAAAGGUCUGUCUUGAUGUGACAUCGGUGGAGCCUUCCUCUGAGUGUGUAGGAGAACCCUACCAUGUGGUUAUUCAUGGAAAUGGCUUUCAGAAUCUAAAGAAACGGGAUGAAGUUAUUUGCAGAUUUAUCUUCAAUGAAAGCACUAUCAUUGAUGAAAAGCCAACCAGUAUCGACAAUAAUUCCAUGAAUUGCCCUGGGCCAAAACUAGAAAAACCUGGAGAGGAGUACUCUAUUGAAGUCAGCUUGAACAAAGGCAAAACAUUCUUCAAGAGCAAUGUCAGCAUCACCAGCACCACAUGUGGCAUUUUCCGCAACUGGCUCUAUUUUGUGCCACUCCUGCUGCUUGUGCCACUGCUGCUGUGUUGUGUCUGGCGGCUGUGCCGCAAGCAGACUGUCAAGGAGCCACCACCUGUGCAGAAGCCAGAAAAGGAGCCAGAGCAGGAAAAACCACCAUCACCACCACCACCGCCUCCGCCUCCACCACCUCCACUCCCGCCUCCGCCCCCAGCUCCUGUAAACACCUGCCCCACUGUGAUUAUUUGUUGCUGUGGAUGCCAAGGAGUGGGCGGGAUGAGAAGGAUAGAGGGCAAUCUGGAUACCUUUUGUGACCUCUCUCACGCAAGCUGCCACCAGGUGCCAUGGAUGUGUUGUCAGAGCAGGGACCAGGGGAGGUACCUCAGCUUAGCCCUUGCACAGUCCCAAUAUGCACAGGCUCCCUGCUGCCCAAGGAUCUGCUUUCCACACAGCCAGGAGUGCCUUUCCCUACCACAGGCUCCCUGCAGCCCAAGGAUGUGCCUGAGACACAGCCGGGAGUGCCUCGCCCUCAAACAGGCUCGCUGCAGCCCAAACAUCUGCCUGAGACACAGCCAACACAGCAGGGAGUGCCUUGCCCGCAAACAGGCUCCCUGCAGCCCAAGGAUCUGCCUGAGACACAGCCCGGAGUACUUUUCCCAAGCACAGACUCUGUGCAACCCAAAGAGCUGCCUUCAACCCAGCCGGGAGUGCCUCCCCCUCACCUGCUCCUCCAGGUGCCGCCUCCCCCCAGCUAGGUGCUUGAGGCCUCCCUCCAGGAUGCUGCCGCUGCUGUCCCCACUGCUCAGGCACACGGCAGAACCCCCUUUGUCACUCCCCCCCUCAGAGCCCAACUUCUAAGGCACCAAACACCCAAGAUUAACAGGCUUUUGUUGCUGAACUGGA